AGUCGCGCAAGCGCGAGCGGCUGUGCGCGGUGCGUGGUGCGUGGUGCGUGAUACGAGCGGCGGCACGUGGCGCGGGUGCGGGGCGUGGAGUGGCGUGGCGUGGAGUGGCGUGGCGUGGCGGGGUCUCGCGGCGCGGGCGCGCACCCGGAGCUGUGGACGGAGAGUGCCUCCCUCUGGCCUCAGUUUCCUCAUGUUGUAGUAGCGGAGCAUGGCCCGGACCGGGCCCCCGAGACCGCCCCGUGCAACCUCACCGCCAGCCUGGGGGCCUCAGCGACUGGGACGGGACCAAGGGGCUCGGGGAUUCUCCCUGCCCCCGGCCCUGGUGCGUGACUGACCCUCCUGUUCCCAGAGCCCCCAGCGCAGGCCGGGAUGUUCGUCCUGGUGGAAAUGGUGGACACCGUCCGGAUCCCCCCUUGGCAGUUUGAGAGGAAGCUCAACGACUCCAUUGCCGAGGAGCUGAACAAGAAGUUGGCCAACAAGGUCGUGUACAACGUGGGACUCUGCAUUUGUCUGUUUGAUAUCACCAAACUGGAGGAUGCCUAUGUAUUCCCUGGGGAUGGCGCAUCACACACCAAAGUCCAUUUUCGCUGCGUGGUGUUUCAUCCAUUCCUAGAUGAGAUUCUCAUUGGGAAGAUCAAAGGCUGCAGCCCAGAAGGAGUGCACGUCUCUCUAGGCUUCUUCGAUGACAUUCUCAUCCCCCCAGAGUCACUGCAGCAGCCAGCCAAGUUCGACGAAGCGGAGCAGGUGUGGGUGUGGGAGUACGAGACGGAGGAAGGAGCACACGACCUCUACAUGGACACCGGCGAGGAGAUCCGCUUCCGGGUGGUGGACGAGAGCUUUGUUGACACGUCCCCCACAGGGCCCAGCUCAGCAGAUGCCACCACUUCCAGUGAGGAGCUGCCAAAGAAGGAGGCUCCGUACACGCUUGUGGGAUCCAUCAGUGAGCCAGGCCUGGGCCUUCUCUCCUGGUGGACCAGCAACUAGCCCUGGGGCUGGACAGUGGACCCUACCAGCCUGCGGGAAGGUGGUAUGGCCGGCUGUGAAGACAACAGCAGCUGAGGCCGAUGCUAAGGAGAUAGUGUCUCGAGCUGGACAGUGAGGCAAGGCCAGGAGUGCCCACCAGCUUGCCCCGCUCCUCCACCAUCUAGGCCCUGCUCCUCCUUCACUGCAGUGAUGGAUCCAUCUGUGGCUGUGGCUGUUGGGCCUCCACUGACCUUGACUGAAAAGACCCUUCCUGGACCCUGGACUUGACAACAAACGGCACAGACACCAAUCACUCACAGAACAGUCACUGGUUUUGGAUUCUUGUUUUCCUUGCAAGAACAAAAGGUUCUCUAGAAUCCUUCAGCCACCAAUGAAAUGAUCAGGCAGGAGAAAAACUUUAGAUGGGAGUCUUGUCAUCAAAAAUAAAUACAGUUGCAUGGAGCUGCUUAAGAUCUGAACCAAACUCAAAAUAGGAAGACGGGGGCUAAAAAGUUAUUUUAAGAACCCCCCCACCACAACCACAGUCACUCCGUGGGCUAAGCGGGGAGCAGGAAGCAUGUCUGGUCACACCAUCUUGGAAUAGGAAGCCAUGGCUGGACGGAUCGGAUCCACUGAUGGCACACGUGGAGCUGAACUUGACGCCAGCGGCGGGGCGGGGAGGCACUGCCCUCACUGUUGCAGUUCCUUCAUUCUGUUGAGGGCACUGCCAGCGCGGAACCACUCAAUCUGCGUCUCGUUGAAGGUGUGGUUCAGGAGGAUGGUCUCCUGGGUCCCGUUGGGGUGCUUGAUGAUGCACUUCAGGGGCUGCAAGGAGAAGGUGGGUGUGGGUGGAAGUGGUGGGUACUGUGUGCCCUUGGCCCCGCAGGGGGGUCAGGGAGACAGGGCACUGCCUGGGGACCUAAGAGGUCAGCAGGCAAACCAAAUCCUAGGCCAGUCUGUGCCUGAUGGCCCAGGUCAGACCCAGGUGGCACCUACAGGGGAUUCCUGGGGCCCAGAGGGUCCUGCAGUGGGUGGGCUGUCCCCUGAGUGCCAGGUCCUGGUGAGUAAAGGGAGGUUGGGGAGGUGUGAGGGCCCCGGGUUGACUCCAACCCCCAACUCUGAGAAGCCACUUUGCUUUCUCUGUGGGGCCACCUGGAGAACUGGGGGCCUUUCCAGCUGGAAUGAAGCCUCCUGGGAGAAGCUACCCUGGGGCCAGUGCAGGAGGGGAAACAAGGUGGCUGCCCCUCACCCCACCACCUCAGGGGGACCCGGGCCCCUAACCUUGCCAGGGGUGAAGUCCUUCAGGCCCUGAAUGGUCAGCUUGUCCACAGGGUGAAUCUUGUUGUAGUCAGCCGGGUCAGCGAAGGUCAGAGGCAGCAGGCCCUGUUUCUUCAGGUUGGUCUCUGGAAAGCAGGCGGCAUUCGGUCAUCGGGGGCCUGACUAGCCUGGAGAGCUUCAUUUUCUGAACCCAUCUGGGGCUCUGGGAGAUGCCCCUAAUCCUGCUGCCUGGGACAAUGCCCGGGCAGUGACUAUGGGGCCCUGGUCUGCUCCCUUUCACUAGGGGUGCCCCUAGCAAGUGUGCGCUGGUGCUGAGGUCUGCGAGGCCUUCCUGCUGCACAUUCAUGAUCAGAAAGAACCCCCUGGCACAUGUCCUAGAUCUCAGCGGCUCAGAUCUACAAGCCUGGAAGCAGGGCCUGCGGGAAGCCGGGAAGCUGAGCGUCGGAUGUGCACUGUGUGAGCCUAAGAAGGGGCAAGAGGCUGACGGGCCUGUGGGCUGCAGUGGACACAGCCUAGAACCAGGCCCAACUCAGCCACGGGCAGGGAGAGUGACCUUGAUCACUAGGGAUGGGAUGAGGAUGGCCUGGGUACAGACUCCAGCUCACCGUGGAUCCUGGCAAAGCUCUUGGUGAUGAUGGCCCGGCCCCCAAGGUGGCGAGGCUCCAGAGCUGCAUGCUCCCGGCUCGAGCCCUCGCCGUAGUUCUCGUCUCCGAUCACCACCCACCUGAUGCCAUGUUUCUGUCAGGCAAGCGGGGGUAAGGUUAUAAGGCAGAGGAGGGCACCGUCCUCACCUGUCUGGCCCUACCUGCCUGGCCUCACCCACCUGGCGCCUGGGCAUCCUGAGGCUCCCGGUAAAGGGGCUGGAGGGGCCCUUCCUCGCCUGCUGCCUAAGGGCAAGUGAAGCCUGCGUGAAUGAGACCCAAACGAGGCCCCGAGGGGACAGAGGCACGUGGUUGUUUGCAGUGGCAAAGAAGACAGAAGCCACCCAUUGGUGCUUGGCAGAGGCAGGUGUGUGUGGAGGGAGGUUGGGUGAGACAGGGACGGCCUCCGGGCCCCACACAAGAUGCAUCUGUGAAGCUCAAGGCGCCCCCUUCCUGGGAGCACCCUCUGCCCCACCCAGCCACCAGGGGGUGCCAGAGUCCUUUCACCCGGCUGGGCCAGGACUUGGGUUCAGCCCUGGUUCUGUUUGUUUCUCAAAGCAGAAAAAGUCCAAUCACCUCAGACCCUCUCUGCCUGCUCACUGUGAGGCCCCGUGUAGCCCCCUCUCUGAGCUUUUGGCCUCUGACUUCCUGAGUCGGCCCCCUUCCUUGUCUUUGUCUAGGGCCAGAUAUCCUAAGAUAUCUCUCACUAACUCCUCCUGGUGCAGGGACCCGGCUGUACCACCGGACCUGGGCCUCAUGCCUUCUCAGCCACAGGGAGGGGCUGCAGGCCUCUCCUCCCUUCCACAGCAGUCCCCUUUGGGCUUGGUCGGCCUCCUUCCCAGUUUCCACUCCCCUAAUGUCCUCCCUGCACCUGCCUUGCAGGCCCCUUCAGGAGUGACCACUGGCAUUGCCCCUAUCAACUCUGACCCACCUUGUAGUAGCGGGCAGUGUCAGGGACGGGGCCAAACUCCUGAGUGACGGCAUUGCGCACGGAGUUGGCCUUGCCGUUUUCAAUGUUGAUGGCACCAAUGAGCAGGUUGUUGGAGAUGUUAUCCAAGUGCCCACGGAACUUGAGCCAGGGGCCAGCAGCUGAGAUGUGGUCAGUGGUACACUUCCCUUUGACCUUGGGUGGUAAGUAGAGAGGACAGAGGUCAGGGCAUGGCCCUGGAGGGGUGGAUGACAAGCCCUCCAGAGGCAGGCAGCAGGCCCCGGGGCCCAGGAGGGGUGACAGAGGGGUGAGAGGCAGGCAAGUCUUCAGACACGUGUUCUGUGGUCCUGGUGCUUCCACCCUAAGGCCACAUGGGCUCAGGCCAGGCCUUCAUCCCCUCAAAGGCCUCUGGCUGCUCAGUCUCCCUUAUGGGGCAGAGGCCGCCCAAAGUUGGGACAGGUCAAUGUUCGCUCACCCUUCAGGCCUCAGCUGCAAGAUCAGCCACAGACCUCAUGCUGGACACAGGAGCCCAGGACAUGCCUGGGUCCUGGCUGAUGACUGAUUAGUCUCUUCUGUCACAGGGGUGCCUGGAGACCCCUUAAUAAGCAGCAUAAAUAAAUAUCUGACACAGAUUGGAGGCCUCUGGCCACACCAAAAA